GUUGUCGGCCAGUGCCUUCCGUGAAGUUGCUCGCCGGGUCGUUGGGCCCUGUCGACCUGUAGGCGGGCGAGCGAGCCAGCGGACAAGACUGCGGGUGAGGCUGAGCUAGCGAGCGGCCGGCAGGGGGGGCGCCCGGGCUGCGAGCCGCUGAGCCCAGCCGCGCUGCCGCCGCCGGCCGUCGUGGGGCCGGAAUGGCGCAAGGCCGGAGUGGCGCGGGCGCUCGGCGCUGGGCUGCCGGGUAGAGUCCUGUCCCCGCCCCUCGCCUUGCGGCCUGACGCCGGCCGCUGCUGCCCGGGGACCGGAGCGGCGGGCCGCCUUUGCCCAGGACACACGCUCUGGCGUUUGUUCCUUUGGGCGUGACGCCAGCUUCAACGGGUACGCGGCUUUCCCGACGGGUGCUGAUCUCCGAGUCGCUGUUGUCACGCGGACUGCUGUCCUCCAGAUUCAGGCCGGUGGGUCUGGGGAGCCCGGAUUGGUCUUGGAGGAGCAACGGCUGCGCAGGUGACUCGGUGGCCUCAAGUGUGUAGGUACCUGGAUGGCGCGAGGAGAUGCUGGCUCUGAAAUACUUCCCAAUUCCGCUUGCAGAUGAACUCCGGACUAGAGUUUAGGCUACAGACAAGUUAGGCGGUUGAUGUGAUUCUGUAGCUCGUAUUUCGAACUUUAGGGAUGUUUUGAUGUAUCAGUAAAUGUAGAUCUGUGUCACAGUUUUAAUGGCAGCUUCACAUUCCGGAUAUCUUUAUGUUGGGGAAAAUGUUUCAAAGGUACAAAACUCAAAACAUGAACAACAAUAUAUAUUACCAAUCUUCAAACCUGGUUUGCCUAGAACUGGAAUACAGUUGCCUGCGACAUAUUUUAGAAGAACUAGAAAAGUCAAAGUAAUGGAUAACAGAAAAGAGCCUCCAUUCUUCAAUGAUGAUAACAUGGGACCAUUUUACUACAGACUUCAUUUCUGUGAUACCAUGGAGCUCUUCAUUGAAACAUUAACUGGAACAUGUUUUGAGCUGAGAGUUUCACCUUUUGAAACUGUUAUUUCUGUGAAAGCAAAAAUUCGAAGAUUGGAAGGUAUUCCCAUCUGUCGACAACACUUAAUUUGGAAUAACAUGGAACUUGAAAAUGAUUAUUGCUUGAAUGAUUACAACAUUUCAGAAGGGUGUACCUUGAAGCUAGUUUUGGCUAUGCGUGGCGGACCUAUAAAUACUAGAAGAGUUCCUACAGACGAUCCACUUAGGAAGAUGGCAGAGUACUUGGAUUCCAGUCGAGUUGAGGUCUGGGAGAAGACCUCCUGCAGCAAACAAGUUACAUUUUUGGUAUACCAAGAAGGAGAUCAAUUGAAUUUCUUUCCUGCAGUAGAUAGGGGAGAUGGCACUUUAACACCGUUAUCUGACUCUUCAAAGAAAAUAGAUUUUCAUUUGCAUGUCCUACGGAGAAAAGGAGAACAUCGUAUGAGUUAUUGUUUUCUUUGCAGUGGUGGUUCUAUGUAUAAUUCAGAUACAGAUGAGGAUGAAGAAACUGAGCCUUCUUCUUCUGGGCAACAGAUAAUUGAAAAUUCAAUAACUAUGAAUAAGAUGAAGCUGCUGAAGGCUAAGAUGAAGAACAUGAAUCUCAGCAAAAAGCCUAAGAAAGCUGUCAAGAUAAAACCUCACCCACCUGUAGCUCCUCGACCUUCUAGUGGUUCCACUGCACCAUCUCGCCACCGAUUGUUAAGGGUCCUCCCCAACAUUGGUCAAUCUUGUUCACCUGCUUUUGGGAAUGCAUAUCCGCCCGAAAUCUCCAGGAAUGGAAUUUCAAGUUUGGCAACUCAACUCUCUGCUGAGAGAUACAUAUCUUCUAUCACUGGUGAAUUUCUUAAGGAAGAUAAUAGCUGGGAGAAUAACACACUGUCUCACUUCAGUAGCAACGUCAAACUACCUCCUCAGAUACCCCAUUUGGAGUUGGGAAAUGACCAGGAGCUUGCUGACUCUGUUCUCCAUCUUGGAUCAUCCCUGCCUAGGCAAACAAAACAUUUUUUAGGAAACUUGCCAUCUAGUAAUGGGAACAUUGUCUUACCUUCAGAAGAAUGUGUAACCGAACAAUCACUUCUACCUAAAGUGGGCUCACUGGCUUCAUUUGCAGAAGGAAAUGCUGAUGAACAGAGCAGCGGCUUAGAAGGUGCGUGCAAAGUGAAUCUGGAGUUGCUACUCACUAAUGCUGACAAAGGGUUGAAAGCUCCAGAGCAGCAUCUCAAGCAUGUUGCAGGAGUGCUGAAUGGGGAAUCAGUAGAGACUUCAGUUCUUAACUACCGGGAAUUAAGUCCUCACAAGAAUAGACUCUUGUCACCUCUUCGCUGUUCUGCACCAAUGUCGCUACAUAAUUCUCUGGUGAAACCAGAGAGACAGUCCAAAUGUUUUGAGUUUGGGAAGCUACAGCCUUCUUCUUCUCAGUCACUGGAUGUUCAAAACAUAACUGAUUCUUCUUUCUCUAGGACUACUUGCUUUCAAGGUGUUAAAGUUGAUUCACUUGGGAAAAGAUCUGAUGUUAUUUCCAAAGUUGAGGCUCGGGAUAUCACAGAAAUGACUAACAAGGCUUCCAAAGAGCCUGUUGGUUGUGUAAAUAAUAUCAGUUUUCUUGCCUCACUGGCCGGGAGCACAAGCAGAAAUAGAUUACAGAGCACACGUGGGGCAGGCAGGCUUCAGAACUCUGGAACUGGGCUGUCUACAAACCUCCAGCAUUUUCAGGAAGAAAACUUUAGGAAAAGUUCUCCCCAGUUAGAACAUACAGGAGUUUUUUUGUCUACCCAUGGUGUUGGAAUGAAUGGAAAUAAUGCAGCAGCAGGGAAAAGCGUAGGAGAAUGUACUACUCAUCACCUCCCACCUGUGAAAGCCCCUCUUCAGACAAAGAAGAAAACAACAAAUCAUUGUUUUCUUUGUGGAAAGAAAACAGGACUGGCUAGUAGCUACGAAUGCAGAUGUGGAAACAACUUCUGUGCAUCUCAUCGUUAUGCAGAAACUCAUGGCUGUACCUAUGAUUACAAGAGUGCAGGGAGGAGAUACUUGCACGAGGCAAAUCCUGUGGUUAAUGCACCAAAGCUUCCAAAAAUCUAACUCUUCCUCUACAUCUUACUGUUCUGCCCGGGAUUCGUAUUAUAAUGACAGAAGAAAUGUUGUUUAGACUAUUAUUUUUGUUCGACUCUAAAAGAUUUGCCAAAUAACAAAAGCAUACAAUGCAUACUGUUGGAGAACAAGAAUGCUACUGUAUUUUACAUCUUUAUUUCUUGGUGAAACAAAAGUUUUAAAAGUAGUUUUAACAACUUUACACUGGAAUGAUUUAGCUUUGUUAUUGCAUGUCUUGUGUUAAGUGUUUUGUAUAUGAUAUUGCAGUUUUACUAGGCAAAUCUUCAAAAGAUGCACUUUAGGAAACGAAAUAUUUCCUAAAUAACCAGGCUUCCACAUUGUACAGAAUGAGCAGUCAUGUAAUGAAUGGCUCUACUCAGAUUGACCAUAUGGGUUUUUUCUUUUUCUUUCUUUUAUUCUUCUCCUUCUUUUUUUUUCAGAGGUGGGAUGGGUGGAGAUUUUUUAAAAAUCCCACGUGUGAAAGUUUACUGGCUUUAUUAGCAAGUUCCUUUUUACUUCAAGCUACUUUUUAUAAAAAAGAACAUUUUUCCAGUGUGGUUUUUAACAGAUAAUACAUUUCUUCCACAUUCAGAUUAGUAUUCGGACAUGAAUCCAUUCUAUAAAACACAUCGUGUUCAUGAUAGUGUAUAUUUUACUACUUUUUGAAUGUUAAUUUUAAAAUAGAAGAUGUCCCACUUGCCAUUAAAUAUAGAAGCCAACUUUUUACCUUUUGAAAUAUGGCUACAUUUAAAACAAAAUCUCACAGCUCGGUUUUUCUUAUUUGUUGAGUGCUAUUACCAGGAGAAAUUCAAAUAAAUAUUCAAUUUCAUUAUGAAUUUCAUUAUUUAUUUAUAAUAGUUUUUCUUUUAUAAAUAAUUUUUCUUUUAUAAAACUAUUUAAUUAAAUGAGUGAUUUAUUUUACGUGGA